GGGUACCGCUGCUGGCUAGCGACCGACGAGCAACCGUCUGAGGCCAGGAGCGCUGCGACGGAGCCUUGACCGCCGUUGCCCGGCCCUCUCCCGCGCAGCCCCGGGCUUCCGCAGUCCUUCCUUCAGAAGGGAAAUUUCUGAGGGUCAGGAAGGGGAAUCUGUACCUCACUCCUUGAACACCAAGGAAGGAAUAUUGGGAAACCAAAAUGAGGCACAAUCAGAUGUGUUGUGAGACACCACCUACUGUCACUGUUUAUGUAAAAUCAGGGUCAAAUAGAUCACAUCAGCCUAAAAAGCCCAUUACUCUGAAGCGUCCUAUUUGUAAAGAUAAUUGGCAAGCAUUUGAAAAAAAUACACAUAAUAACAACAAAUCUAAACGCCCCAAAGGACCUUGUCUGGUUAUACAGCGUCAGGAUAUGACUGCUUUCUUUAAAUUAUUUGAUGACGAUUUAAUUCAAGAUUUCUUGUGGAUGGACUGCUGCUGUAAAAUUGCAGACAAGUAUCUUUUGGCUAUGACCUUUGUUUAUUUCAAGAGGGCUAAAUUUACUAUAAGUGAGCAUACCAGGAUAAAUUUCUUUAUUGCUCUGUAUCUGGCUAAUACAGUUGAAGAAGAUGAAGAAGAAACCAAGUACGAAAUUUUUCCAUGGGCUUUAGGGAAAAACUGGAGAAAAUUGUUCCCUAAUUUCUUAAAGUUAAGGGACCAGCUCUGGGAUAGAAUUGACUAUAGGGCUAUUGUAAGCAGGCGAUGUUGUGAGGAGGUUAUGGCCAUUGCACCAACCCAUUAUAUCUGGCAAAGAGAACGUUCUGUUCAUCACAGUGGAGCUGUCAGAAACUACAACAGAGAUGAAGUUCAGCUGCCCCGGGGACCUAGUGCCACACCAGUAGAUUGUUCACUCUGUGGUAAAAAAAGAAGAUAUGUUAGACUGGGAUUGUCUUCAUCAUCAUCUUUAUCCAGUCAUACAGCAGGGGUGACAGAAAAACAUUCUCAGGACUCAUACAACUCACUGUCAAUGGACAUAAUAGGUGAUCCUUCUCAAGCUUAUACUGGUUCUGAAGUAGUCAAUGACCAUCAAUCAAAUAAAGGAAAGAAAACUAAUUUCUUGAAGAAAGACAAAUCUAUGGAGUGGUUUACAGGAAGUGAAGAAUGAGAUGGCCCAACUAAACCAAUUUGGAAUCAUUAACUACAAAAUGUCAAACUAACUGCAAGACAAGUGUCAAAAUGGGAUGUUUAAGCAGUUUUGCUAUGUUAUACAUCUUUUAGUUGUUAUUUUCAAAAUUAUAUGUAUAAGUUAUAUAAGUCAUAGUAAUAGCUAAAAAUGCCAAUCUAUGGAAGCAGUGAUUUUCAAUAUAAAGUUCUAUUUUGAUAUUUUUCCAUCUUCAAGUCAGUUACUGUCAUCUGGAGUACUCAGUUAAGUUGUGGUUUGACCUUCCUCAACUUGACAAGAAAAGCUAAUUUAAGAGAAGAAAAACAUAAAGUCAUUAUAUUAAUUAAAAGAAAAAACACCAUUUAAUAUGUUCUGAAAACAUUACUCACCUGUAUGACCAGGUUGCCAGUGUACUGGUCUAGCAACAUAGGGAAAUGAUCCAUAUGGAAAAUCAGAAUGCGAUUCUUCUGUUGUAAAAAAAUAUAUGUACUAUAAGCUACAUAAAAUAUUUUCUAUUUUUUUCACAAAACUGUUAAAAUAUGAGUUACUCUCUUUAUUGUAAGUUUUUUCUUUAUUUAUUUCCUUGCAUAUGUUUUAGAGCUACUCUGCCAGUUAUUAUACAGAAACUAUUUGUCAAUGAUUAUGUAAUAAACAUAUGAUUUUAUAACCAAA